AGCUCAGCAAGGCAGAUGGCAGUGGAGGGGGUGUCUGCUUCUCCUAUGAGAGAAAUGAGAGGAAAAUAACCAUAGUAUGCAACCUUUGAUGCUCUGCCUAUCCAAGGAGAAGCAUGCACAUUUCUUACUGUCCAGGGCACACACCCAUCUCACCACACAGAGGCACCUCCAAGCAUGGCCUGGGUGAAAUGCUGCUAUUGACAGAUACAGACAGUCUGGUACAUGGAAAAUAAUCCAACUUGUUCAUCUUGGAGUGUUGUUAGCUCUGGGCAAAUUCCAACCCUAAUCCUGACCAUCCUUAUUCAUUUAAGUACCCUCAGCAACUCAUCAGCCACAGAGGCUUACCCAAGGUUACCCAUAACCCCACAUUAAGGUCCUAUGAGGUAACAACAUCACAAUCACAAACAAAACUGCAGACACGAUGUCCUAAGAACAUAAGUCAGAAUUUUAUCUACAUCUUUCCCUCCUUCAUCAGCCUCAAAAUGCACAGUUCCUGACCACACACACUUUGGGUUUAGACUCCAUGUGGGCAGAAGCAUCUGUGUCAGUUGCAUACCUAGGUGUGACAGUGAGUGCUGGGAACACAACUGGCUCUCAGAGUCCUUGUUUUCUCCCUUCCCAAAUGCUGAGUCCCAGCUAGAGCUCAUUUUAAUACAGAUCGAGUUCAGCUCCUCCUUCUCCCACACUCACUCUCACACUCUACUGCCUAUAGUAUCCUCACUGCAACAUGGUCACGGGAGUGUCCUGAUGUCAGUUACCUCCCAUCAGUGGCCAUAGACAGAAUGAGGCUGAACUGUCUCCAGUCUUUCAGUUAGAGGACUCUGGCUUCUGGAAAGACUGACCAUAUCCAAAGCAGCUCUCUAAUGAGGAGAAGGGGUGAGAAUGGGAUUCCCACUCUCAGGAGAGGUCAGAGAGUCCUGCUGAGGGCAACAGGAGAUGGUGGCACUAUCAAAGGUCAUGGUGAAUGAUAAGAUGAUUUUAACAUAGAAGGAAAAGAAAAGGAGCUCUAGUUUCAAAAUAUCAUCAUCAUCAACAACAAACAGAAAAUGAUGUGGUCAGAUAAAAGAAGACCCUACAGAACAUGAUGUGGUAGUAUCCAGAUAGAAUCAGGUCAAUAUUCGUUGGUGACUGAAGCCAGGUGGAUUCUUUGGAGAAUAAACUACAGUGGUUGAAGUGUGAAUGCAAAGAGGGGAAGUGAGGACCCAGUGUGUAGCUGAUUCUUGAAGGAAGUUGGCUGUGAGGGGACAACAGGUGGGAGGAGGUGAUAACUAAAGGAGGACACUUAGCUUUGGGAAGGGGGUUUAUGAGAUGGUGAAGACUUGAGCCCGUUGUCAAGCUAGGGGAAAGAUCCUGAUGAACUGGAGAGGGUGAAGAUGAAUUGGUGUCAGUUACAUUGCUGGACAUGUAUCUCCACUCCUUGCAUCAGCUAGGGAGAGAAGAUCUCAUCUCCAUUUUACAGUGAGGCGUCUGACAUAGAGGAGCGCCACUCUCCCCGCUAGUAGUCAGAACAUGACUUGCAGUCACUGCUGUGAGGCUAGCUUUUCCUCUAACUUCAUUCAGUUCACACUUUUCAACCCUUAUACAACUUUUUGUCUUCUUCAUAGGCUCUUUCCCCUGUUGAACACUUGCACUCUAGUGUUAGGUGAAUUUCAGACCUCAGCAUAUUUCUCUACACAGAAUGUGAAAUCAUCCAAGAAGAUGCCAAAUUGAGAGUGCCAUUCUCAUCUCAGAUGAUGAUGAACAGAGAACCUUUCAAGAUGAGUACGAAAUUUCCGAAAUGGUAGGCUACUGUGCUGCGAGGAGUGAGGGGUUGCUACCAUCAUUUCAUACCAUCUCUCCAACCCUCUUCAAUGCCUCAUCCAAUGAUAUGAAGUUAAAACCAGAGCUAUUUCUGACACAGCAAUUUUUGAGCGGGCAUUUGCCAAAAUACGAACAAGUUCACAUCCUCCCAGUAGGAAGAAUAGAGGAACCCUUCUGGCAAAAUUUCAAGCAUCUACAAGAGGAGGUUUUCCAGAAAAUAAAGACACUGGCUCAGCUCUCAAAGGAUGUUCAGGAUGUCAUGUUCUACAGUAUCCUGGCCAUGCUCAGAGACAGAGGGGCUCUACAGGACCUGAUGAACAUGCUGGAAUUGGACAGCUCAGGUCAUUUGGAUGGCCCUGGUGGUGCCAUCCUAAAGAAACUUCAACAGGAUUCAAACCAUGCAUGGUUUAACCCAAAGGACCCCAUUCUUUAUCUCCUUGAAGCCAUAAUGGUGCUGAGUGACUUCCAACACGAUUUGCUGGCCUGUUCCAUGGAGAAGAGGAUCCUGCUUCAGCAACAGGAGCUGGUAAGGAGCAUCCUGGAGCCAAACUUCAGAUACCCCUGGAGCAUUCCCUUCACCCUCAAACCUGAGCUCCUCGCCCCACUCCAGAGUGAGGGUUUGGCCAUCACCUAUGGCCUGCUGGAGGAGUGUGGCCUUAGGACGGAGCUGGAUAACCCCAGGUCAACCUGGGAUGUAGAAGCAAAGAUGCCCCUGUCUGCCCUCUAUGGGACUCUCUCGUUGCUGCAGCAGCUGGCUGAGGCCUAAGCCCUCCCUGAUGGGCAGUCAGUCCAGAGAUGCUGGCCCUCGCCCAGUCUAUGCUGUGAGUGUCCUUAUGGGUGCAAGAGAUAGGGCUGUGCCUCUCUGCGUUUCCAGGUGGAGUAGAGACAGUAAUGGGUAGAGACUUUAGGAAAUGUUUUGGGGUGGUGGAAUACUCUAUAUAUUGACAAGAGUUUAUAUAUUGACAAGAGUUUAUAUAUUUGUCAAAACUCCUCAAAUAGUAUGUUAAAGACGUAAGCGUUUCACUAUGUAUAAAUUUUACUUCAAAAUAAUAAAAACAAAUACUGACUCUA